UAGUACCCGGAAUGCUAGGAAAAUGUCCUCUAACUCAACAGUUAAUACCCUGGAAGAGUGGAGACUCAACAGGCGAUUGCUCAGGGCGUCUGAGCCUUUCGCUAGGGAAACCGUUUAGUUUACGUUACUAAAGUCCCCCCUGUCCGUGUCUGUCACUUGGACUCGCCUACUGACUGAGCAAAAGGACAGACUACUUCAAAAUAGAAAAGGAAUUCGGGGCGAGCCAGAGAGGGCCCACACGACUAGAAGGACGACUGCCUGGCGCGAUACAAAAAUAUCUGCCGACACCCCAGGCCAUCGAGCCCCAGGCCAUCGUGCAGCAGGUCCCAGCCCCCAGUCGAAUGCAGAUGCCGCAGGGGAACCCGCUGCUGCUGUCCCACACCCUGCAGGAGCUGCUGGCCAGGGACACCGUGCAGGUGGAGCUCAUUCCGGAGAAGAAGGGCCUCUUCCUGAAGCAUGUGGAGUAUGAGGUUUCCAGCCAGCGCUUCAAGUCCUCGGUAUACAGACGGUACAAUGACUUCGUGGUCUUCCAGGAGAUGCUCCUGCACAAGUUCCCCUACCGUAUGGUGCCUGCCCUGCCACCCAAGAGAAUGCUGGGAGCUGACAGGGAGUUCAUCGAGGCCAGGAGGAGAGCCCUGAAGCGCUUCGUCAACCUGGUGGCGCGACACCCCCUGUUCUCCGAGGAUGUGGUCCUCAAGCUCUUCCUGUCCUUCAGCGGCUCGGAUGUGCAGAACAAGUUAAAGGAGUCAGCACAGUGCGUCGGGGACGAAUUCCUGAACUGUAAGCUGGCUACCAGGGCCAAGGACUUCCUCCCAGCUGACAUCCAGGCUCAGUUUGCCAUCAGCCGGGAGCUGAUCCGGAACAUCUACAAUAGCUUUCACAAGCUUCGCGACAGGGCCGAGCGGAUCGCAUCGCGGGCCAUCGACAAUGCGGCAGAUCUUCUCAUAUUCGGGAAGGAGCUAAGUGCAAUAGGGUCUGACACGACCCCGCUGCCCUCCUGGGCCGCUCUGAAUAGCAGCACGUGGGGGUCCCUGAAGCAGGCUCUGAAAGGCCUGUCUGUGGAAUUCGCGCUGCUCGCCGACAAGGCUGCACAACAGGGUAAGCAGGAAGAGAACGACGUGGUGGAGAAGCUGAACCUCUUCUUGGAUCUGCUGCAGUCCUAUAAGGACCUGUGCGAGCGGCAUGAGAAGGGCGUGUUGCACAAGCACCAGCGGGCCCUGCACAAGUACAGCCUGAUGAAGAGGCAGAUGAUGAGCGCCACCGCGCAGAACCGCGAGCCGGAGUCCGUGGAGCAGCUGGAGUCCCGCAUUGUGGAGCAGGAGAACGCGAUUCAGACGAUGGAGCUGCGGAACUACUUCUCCCUGUACUGCCUGCACCAGGAGACGCAGCUCAUCCACGUCUACCUGCCCCUCACCUCCCACAUCCUCCGCGCCUUCGUCAACUCUCAGAUCCAAGGGCACAAGGAGAUGAGCAAGGUGUGGAACGACCUGAGGCCCAAGCUCAGCUGCCUCUUUGCGGGACCACACAGCACCCUGACCCCACCGUGCUCCCCGCCGGAGGACGGCCUGUGUCCUCACUAGCGCCUGAGGCUGAGGUGGUGCUCCCUGCGGCCGCACUAAAACCUCUUUCCAAACGGUGUGUCCCGGUGUAAUUCCCUUUGGACGGCAGCUCCCCUCCCCGCCACGCCCCGUGCUGCAGCUGGAGCAGAGGAGCUCACGCCUGCGGGUCGGGAGGCGCAUCCGUGGACCAUGGGGGCAGCUGGGCCACACUGUCCUUCGCCCUGUGGCCUGCUAGCCUGGUCGAGAGAGGUGGUGGGGUUCUCUGGAAUGGUUUCCUCCUGACACCCAGAGCUGUGCGGGGAGGCAGGGAUCUCUCAUCUCACAGAGAUUGUGCCUGGGGGAGCGUGGAGGCAGGGCCUCCAGGUGCUGGAACAGUCGGGAGGGGCAGCAUCAUGGUGCUCGGUCAGCCGAGGAGAGAGGGCAGGGCUGCCCUGCAGCCCAGGCAUGGGACUGACCACGGACAGCGAGGGGACAGCCAGUGGUGCUGAGGCUGGGAGGGAGGGCCAUUGGGCGUGGGGCACGCACGGUGAAUUUUCUAGGGAAAUUGCUGCAGUCAACACCUGGAGCCCUGGUCUGGGAGUGGCCUGUGGGGUCCAGUGGCCUCAUGCCCUGUGCCCAUAUGAUGACCCCAUGUGUGCCUGUGUCCACACCAUGACCCUGUGUGUGCCCAGGCCUGGAAGACAAAGGCGUGACGGAGAGCUGGGGCUCUGAGAGUGGGCGCUACAGCAGCUGUGUUCUCGUCCCCUGGACUCCCUUGAUUUCUGGUGGCCAGUGUUGGGGUCUGCACCGUGUGGCACUGAGGCUGGAUGGGCUGGCAGAGGACAGGUGGGGGCGUGGGGGGGCGUGUUCCAUUCCAGCUGAGGCUUUAGAGGAGGGACAGCCCCCUUUUAAGUGGAUUUCCUUCUCUGAGGCACCUAGAGCCCUCCUCCCAGCCUCCCGUCACGCACUUGCCGGCCCAGCCACCUGCUCACAGAGGGAACCAGUGGUCUUUCAGGCCCCUUCCCUGCUCUGGAUGAAGAAGGCCAUUCUCCUGAGCUCUGUGGGGCUGGACUGUCCGCCUCAGGCCUGGGUCUGCUUCUGCCCGAACCCCUUUUGUGGAAGGUACAUGGGAGCCCAGUGGACCCCUGCACUUCUCCGGAGCCUGACGCCCCUCCCUGGCCGGGGAGGGGUGCUGGAAGAGGCCCGCCGGGCUCCAGGGUUUCCGAGGUCCCUCCGCUCCGCAGAUGCUCACUGGCCUCUGGGGCGUUCACUCCUCUCACGGAGGGUGCUUCCCUUCCGCCUGUACCUACGGGCAGCUCACGGCCGUGGGAUGGAGAGGGGACUCCUGUGUGUGCCCCGCAGGCAGGUGAUCCAUCGUCCACUGCGAGCCGGCCAGAGGGAACGGCCGUGCCUUCUGGCCCCGUGGGCUGUGCUGACUCGGUGGCUGUGGGGCUCGGGCCCAGCCUGCCCUGCCCUGUGGGUUCUGCUGCUGCCUUCCUGCUGUGAGGUGGGCUGCUUCCUUCUGGCCAGAUGAGCAGAGGGCAGCGUUCCCUUUGGAGCCCGAUGGGUGGGCUGUCCCGUGAGUCCCUAGUCCACCCGAGUCUUGGGCUGCGCUGCCUUCUGACGCCCCUCUGCAGAGACAGGUUCUCAGUUGCCAUGAAUGGCACCAUGACACCCGAGCCAUGAAGCGUGACCCCGUGUGGGCAGAAGGCUGCAAGGCCUCUCCGUCCACCCCGCACCUUCCUGGGGCCUGUCCAGCUGCAGGACCAUAGAGGCUGUGGGGAGUCGUGGAGGGCAUCAGGUGCUGGGGCCUCUGUGUCUCCAGAGUAGGCAAGGCACGCGCUCCUGACAGCCCCCAAGGAUUGAGCAAGACUUCAGAAUGAGCUUUUCUGAAGGAGCUUUCCUGGCAGGGACUCCGGGGUCAGUGAGUGUAUGAGAGGCCACAUACCUGGCGGCAUCUCCCUGUGUUGGAAACUUCAAGAGCAGGGUCUCAGGGUCCUCAUGUCCAGAGGCUGAGGAUGGAGGUGGAAGGCUGGAGGGCAGGGGUGAGGAGGGAGCAGGAGGGCAGGAGUUGGGGGAGCAGGAGGGCAGGGGUCAGGAGAACAGGAGAACAGGGGUAAGGGAGGGCAGGGGUGAGGGGGAGCAGAAGAGGGAUGAGGGGGAGCAGGAGGGCAGGCGUUGGGACAGGAGGGCAGGGGUGAGAGAGCAAGGGGGCAGGGGUGAGAGAGCAGGAGAGCAGGGGUGAGGAGAGCAGGAGAGUAGGGGUGAUGGGGAAUAGGAGGGCAGGGGUGAGGAGGGAGCAGGAGAACGGGUAAGGGAGGGCAGGGGUGAGGGGGAGCAGGAGGGCAGGGGUGAGGAGAGAGCAAGAGGGCAGGGGUGAGGAGAGCAAGAGGGCAGGGGUGGGAAGGCAGGAGGGAGGUGGGGGGGCAGGAAGGCAGGGGUGGGAGGGUCAGGAGGGCAGGGUGAAGGGGGGGCUGGAGGGCAGCGGUGACGAGGGCAGCCUGUCUCCCACGUGUGGUGGCUGCUUCCUGUGUGCCCUGGGGUUGGCUCUGUGGAGGGGUGGGCACUGGCUUUGGAACACCUCCCUCCCCUUCCUCCUCUGCCACCCAGUGCCUUCUAAAGGGCAGCAGAAAGAGGCCUGCUAGGCAGGGGUGGCGGAGGCCACCUUCCUUCUCACAAAUACUUCUUGGCCCUGGCCCUGUGCUGCCCGGGCAGGUCCCCAGGCUCAGGGGCUGAGAGGCUGCUUACUGCUGCAGGUGGAGGCCCCAUGCCGGAGGGAGAGCGGGGUUCCCCCCAUGCCUCUCCAGCCCUCCUGCUGCCCACGGCCCAAGCCCAAGCUUGUGCCGGUCAUUACGGCCUUGCCUAGCUGGCAGGGACAGCUGCGUGUGAUGCUGGUGGAGAUGCCAGAUGCCGCCUGCCCUGUGAGGACGGCUGGCGGGGCCGUGGGAGGGGGGUUGUGGGCUGGCGGGGCUGUGGGAAGGGGGCUGCCGAUCAUGGUGAAAGGGGACAUUUUCAUUGGGUCCUCGUGGUCCGUGUCCUGGGUACUCGGGGUCACCGUGCAGACAGCUGCCCUUUGUCUGCCGGACACAGUGCAGGCAGGGGAGACAGGUUUAGGGCUCUGACAUGGGGCACAGGGACUCCGAGCCAAGGGAUGUCAGGGCAGCUCUGUGCAUCUGAGGCCUUUGCCCUUGCUUUGCGGGUCAGUUCAUGUCCAAAGCACUUUAGGAGGCUGCAGGGAUCAAUACCCAAUAUACCCAACAACUGGAAUUGUUUACACAUGACCUACAUUUUGGACGGUUUAUCAAUAAACAUGUGUGAACAACUGUUA